AGUCUCAGGAACGUUACUGAUUGAAUUUUUUACGUCAUGUCGGGACGUGGCAAGCAGGGCGGCAAAGCUCGCGCCAAGGCUAAGACCCGUUCUUCAAGGGCGGGUCUUCAGUUCCCAGUGGGCCGAGUGCACCGACUGCUCCGCAAGGGCAACUACGCUGAGCGGGUCGGUGCCGGAGCGCCGGUGUACCUGGCGGCGGUGUUGGAGUACCUAACCGCCGAGAUCCUGGAACUGGCUGGCAACGCGGCCCGCGACAACAAGAAGACCCGCAUCAUCCCGCGCCACUUGCAGCUGGCCAUCCGCAACGACGAGGAGCUCAACAAGCUGCUUGGUAAAGUGACCAUCGCCCAGGGUGGUGUCCUGCCCAAUAUCCAGGCCGUGCUGCUGCCUAAGAAAACUGAGAGCCACCACAAGGCCAAGGGCAAGUAGCGGGGCUGGAGCAGUUCAUUACUCAUACCUCGGUCCAAACCAAAAAGGUUCUUUUCAGAGCCACCUA